AUGCGGAAGAUGGCGGCGUCCAAGGGAGGUUGAGGGCUCUGAGGAGGCGUUGAGAGGUUUCCGUACAGCCCGACCGUGCGGCUUUGGGGAUCCCAUCGCUCUGUGUUUCCUGCUCCAGGUUUCGCGUCUCGCAUCUUCCCAGACCCUCGGGCGCGAUGUGGAGGAGCUGCCUCCGGCUGCGGGACGGGGGACGCCGUCUCCUGAAUCGGCCGGCGGGUGGCCCCAGCGCUUCUAUGAGUCCGGGGCCAACCAUCCCGUCUCCAGCCCGGGCUUACGCCCCGCCGACAGAAAGGAAGAGGUUUUAUCAGAAUGUCAGCAUCACACAGGGUGAAGGUGGCUUUGAGAUAAACCUGGACCACAGGAAGCUGAAAACUCCCCAAGCCAAGCUCUUUACCGUCCCCAGCGAGGCCCUGGCCAUUGCAGUGGCUACUGAGUGGGAUUCCCAGCAGGAUACCAUCAAGUACUACACCAUGCACCUGACCACAUUGUGCAACACAUCAUUGGACAACCCAACCCAGAGAAACAAGGAUCAGCUGAUCCGGGCAGCCGUGAAGUUUCUGGACACCGACACCAUCUGCUACAGGGUGGAGGAGCCCGAGACAUUAGUGGAACUUCAAAGGAAUGAGUGGGAUCCAAUCAUCGAAUGGGCUGAGAAAAGAUACGGCGUGGAGAUCAGCUCCUCCACCAGCAUAAUGGGACCCAGCAUCCCUGCCAAAACUCGGGAGGUGCUCGUCAGCCACCUGGCAUCUUACAACACAUGGGCUUUACAAGGGAUUGAGUUUGUAGCUGCCCAGCUCAAGUCCAUGGUGCUAACCUUGGGCCUGAUUGACCUGCGCCUGACAGUGGAGCAGGCCGUGCUGCUGUCACGCCUGGAGGAGGAGUACCAGGGAGGAUUUCCAUGUCAGCUAGAAAAGUUCAUCCAGCCUGCUAGGAUGGCUUGGGAUUGACUCACCCUGUCUAUUAAACGUGUACACCAAGAGUUGAUUCUGGUCACCAGCUCAUCUUCUCGAUUGUCAAUCUUCAGGAGGUGGAUGUCGUGCGAUGCCCCGACAGCAUUAACAAUCGUAUCUUUAUCGACAAAAAGCUGGUGAGUGAAAAGAAUCCAAUGAGAAAGUGUGUGUCAUUAUACCGUGAACACAAAGGGAGCUGAACAGAGAAGGAGCAUUUGGAAGUCCCCUGGCUGUGCAGGCCACACUCAGAGCAGAGCCCACCUUUGUAUCAGCGCACUCUGCCGAUUCAUCUGUGAAUUCAUCUGUGACAGCCGCUUCCCCAACUGCACAGGGCAGGUGUUGUGGGGAAAGGGCCAACCAGGGUGUUACUUUGCAGUCCCCGCUGGAAGCAUGUUUCCUCCAGGGUGAAGGCAGAUGGCUGCCCAGGGGGCACCUCACCCAGGACAUCUGUUCUCACAAUGCUUCUCUCUCAAUUACUCUCAAGUCUAACUUGCCCAAAACCUCUGCCUGCUGGGUGGAAGCAUGAGGCUGGCUGAGGGUCUCGAGGCUGCUCUGAAGACAGCAGGCCCUACAAACUCAUGGGUGUUCACCCCACAGUUGUCUCUCCACUGCCACUCAUGUCAACAAAACCAAACUUUGGAUUCCAUUUGGAGUAUCCUUCUGCCUUCUCUUGUUCCUGACUUUGCUGUCUUGUAAAAAGUUGUUAGAAACAACCACCUUCUAAUAGGCCUCACUGGUUCUAGGUGUUGACACUGUGGCUAUUGUUGCCUGGGAUGGUUGAAAUGGAGUCAUUUCCCAGAGCAGGGCAAGGCCACUGAAGCACUCAGUAAGCAGUUGCUUCCACCUUGAAGCAGAGGCGCUUGGUAAGGCAGAGCACCUGAAUGCUCUGUAUUGCAGGGAGGAUUUGCAAGUGGAGUGUGCAUUUUUUGUUCUUUCCUGUAGUGGCAGUUAACUUAAUGGUCUCUAAAACGUUCUGUGCAAUCUUAAGAUGUUAAUAUUUCUGCCAAAAAAAGUAUUCUUUGGUCAAAUACAUUUGGGAAAGCCAGCACAUCCUAGGCCCCUCCUAAAGAUUUGCUGGGCACAAAGUAUUCUGAAGGCUCUACAAAGUCCUGUGGAAAAUAAACCCUUUAAGCUUUGUC